CCCCUUUCCUCAGCUGCCGCCAAGGUGCUCGGUCCUUCCGAGGAAGCUAAGGCUGCGUUGGGGUGAGGCCCUCACUUCAUCCGGCGACUAGCACCGCGUCCGGCAGCGCCAGCCCUACACUCGCCCGCGCCAUGGCCUCUGUCUCCGAGCUCGCCUGCAUCUACUCGGCCCUCAUUCUGCACGACGAUGAGGUGACAGUCACGGAGGAUAAGAUCAAUGCCCUCAUUAAAGCAGCCGGUGUAAAUGUUGAGCCUUUUUGGCCUGGCUUGUUUGCAAAGGCCCUGGCCAACGUCAACAUUGGGAGCCUCAUCUGCAAUGUAGGGGCCGGUGGACCUGCUCCAGCAGCUGGUGCUGCACCAGCAGGAGGUCCUGCCCCCUCCACUGCUGCUGCUCCAGCUGAGGAGAAGAAAGUGGAAGCAAAGAAAGAAGAAUCCGAGGAGUCUGAUGAUGACAUGGGCUUUGGUCUUUUUGACUAAACCUCUUUUAUAACAUGUUCAAUAAAAAGCUGAACUUUACUGCUGUUGGUCUUGUCCAUAGUUUUGGAAUGUGCUCUGCAAAAAUGGUCUGUUUUGUAAUGUUGGCUUUCAGCCUAUUCUGCCAUGACACAGGCUGGAUUUUCCCUGCCACCAUUGCCGGAUGUGAGAUUUAGACAAUCCUGAUGCUAACAAGAAGGCACCUCAUGGUACAGUGUUGAAAACUGCACUGGGGUGGCAGGAGGAAGGAUCAGAGCAGAUGCUUUGUCCAGGUUACCUGUGUAAACUUGAUGAUUAUAAGGUGUGUCCCCUACACUGGGGGUGGAGGGUAAUACAGACCAGCUUUAGAAAGCCUCCUGGGUAUUUACCCUAUACAACCCUGCCUAAGAACGAACUUUGACGUAUGCUGAAUGUUGACUGCUACAUCCCAAGGUUGUAAAAAAACAAGACUUAGCUAUGUAAUGUCUCACCAAAUGUUUGGGAGUUUUAUGGUAACACUGAAGGAGUGCAGAAAGUUUACUUAAUAGUUUAUUAAGGUCUCCAGUUACACAAAGUGGAAAAAAAAAAAGAUUCAAACCUGUGUUCCAAAAACUAAGAGCUUUUUUUGUUUGCCAAUUAAUAAUACCAUGAAUGGAAUUUUCAACUUUUCAGGCUUGGAUUUAUAUAAUAAACCGUGGGUAUUGUGUGUUCAGAGCAGCUAA